CUGUGUGCUGCUGAACUGAGCUGGGGCGCAGCCGCCUGUCUGCACCGGCAGCACCAUGUCGCUCAUGGUCGUCAGCAUGGCGUGUGUUGGGUUCUUCUUGCUGGAGGGGCCCUGGCCACAUGUGGGUGGUCAGGACAAGCCCUUCCUCUCUGCCUGGCCCGGCACUGUGGUGUCUGAAGGACAACAUGUGACUCUUCAGUGUCGCUCUCGUCUUGGGUUUAACGAAUUCAGUCUGUCCAAAGAAGACGGGAUGCCUGUCCCUGAGCUCUACAACAGAAUAUUCCGGAACAGCUUUCUCAUGGGCCCUGUGACCCCAGCACAUGCAGGGACCUACAGAUGUUGCAGUUCACACCCACACUCCCCCACUGGGUGGUCGGCACCCAGCAACCCUGUGGUGAUCAUGGUCACAGGAGUCCACAGAAAACCUUCCCUCCUGGCCCACCCAGGUCCCCUGGUGAAAUCGGGAGAGACGGUCAUCCUGCAAUGUUGGUCAGAUGUCAGGUUUGAGCGCUUCCUUCUGCACAGAGAGGGGAUCACUGAGGACCCCUUGCGCCUCAUUGGACAGCUCCACGAUGCGGGUUCCCAGGUCAACUAUUCCAUGGGUCCCAUGACACCUGCCCUUGCAGGGACCUACAGAUGCUUUGGUUCUGUCACUCACUUACCCUAUGAGUUGUCGGCUCCCAGUGACCCUCUGGACAUCGUGGUCGUAGGUCUAUAUGGGAAACCUUCUCUCUCAGCCCAGCCGGGCCCCACGGUUCAGGCAGGAGAGAAUGUGACCUUGUCCUGCAGCUCCCGGAGCUUGUUUGACAUUUACCAUCUAUCCAGGGAGGCAGAGGCCGGUGAACUUAGGCUCACUGCGGUGCUGAGGGUCAAUGGAACAUUCCAGGCCAACUUCCCUCUGGGCCCUGUGACCCACGGAGGGAACUACAGAUGCUUCGGCUCUUUCCGUGCCCUGCCCCACGCGUGGUCAGACCCGAGUGACCCACUGCCCGUUUCUGUCACAGGUAACUCCAGAUACCUGCACGCUCUGAUUGGGACCUCAGUGGUCAUCAUCCCCUUUGCUAUCCUCCUCUUCUUUCUCCUUCAUCGCUGGUGUGCCAACAAAAAGAAUGCUGUUGUAAUGGACCAAGAGCCUGCAGGGAACAGAACAGUGAACAGGGAGGACUCUGAUGAACAAGACCCUCAGGAGGUGACAUACGCACAGUUGAAUCACUGCGUUUUCACACAGAGAAAAAUCACUCGCCCUUCUCAGAGGCCCAAGACACCCCCAACAGAUACCAGCGUGUAACACGGAACUUCCAAAUGCUGAGCGCAGAUCCAAAGUUGUCUUCUGUCCACCAGCACCACAGUCAGGCCUUGAUGGGAUCUUCUAGGGAGACAAUAGCCCUGUCUCAAAACCGGGUUGCCAGCUCCCAUGUACCAGCAGCUGGAAUCUGAAGGCGUGAGUCUGCAUCUUAGGGCAUCGCUCUUCCUCACACCACGAAUCUGAACCAUUGAUGCCUCUCUCUUGCUUACAAAUGUCUAAGGUCCCCACUGCCUGCUGGAGAGAAAACACACUCCUUUGCUUAGCCCACAAUUCUCCAUUUCACUUGACCCCUGCCCACCUCUCCAACCUAACUGGCUUACUUCCUAGUCUACUUGAGGCUGCGAUCACACUGAGGAACUCACAAUUCCAAACAUAUAAGAGGCUCCCUCUUAACACGGCACUUAGAUACAUGCUAUUCCACCUUUCCUCAUGUUGUUCCACCUUUCCUCAGAGUAUCUUUCAGCCUUCUGUCAGCAGUAAAACUUAUAAAUUUUUUUUAUAAUUUCAAUGUAGUUUUCUAUUCUUCAAGUAAACAUGUCUGCCCUCA